UUUUUAUGCCUCAUUCUGUGAAAAUUGCUGUAGUCUCUUCCAGUUAUGAAGAAGGUCCGGUGUUUUCUUACCCACCUCCUUCCCUCCUUUUUAUAAUACCAGUGAAACUUGGUUUGGAGCAUUUCUUUCACAUAAAGGUAACUGCAGAGGCUAUUUCCUGGAAUGAAUCAACGAGUGAAACGAAUAACUCUAUGGUGACUGAAUUCAUUUUUCUGGGUCUCUCUGAUUCUCAGGGACUCCAGACCUUCCUAUUUAUGUUGUUUUUUGUAUUCUAUGGAGGAAUCGUGUUUGGAAACCUUCUUAUUGUCAUAACAGUGGUAUCUGACUCCCACCUUCACUCUCCCAUGUACUUCCUGCUAGCCAACCUCUCACUCAUUGAUCUGUCUCUGUCUUCAGUCACAGCCCCCAAGAUGAUUACUGACUUUUUCAGCCAGCGCAAAGUCAUCUCUUUCAAGGGCUGCCUUGUUCAGAUAUUUCUCCUUCACUUCUUUGGUGGGAGUGAGAUGGUGAUCCUCAUAGCCAUGGGCUUUGACAGAUAUAUAGCAAUAUGCAAACCCCUACACUACACUACAAUUAUGUGUGGCAACGCAUGUGUCGGCAUUAUGGCUGUCGCAUGGGGAAUUGGCUUUCUCCAUUCGGUGAGCCAGUUGGCCUUUGCCGUGCACUUACCCUUCUGUGGUCCCAAUGAGGUCGAUAGUUUUUAUUGUGACCUUCCUAGGGUAAUCAAACUUGCCUGUACAGAUACCUACAGGCUAGAUAUUAUGGUCAUUGCUAACAGUGGUGUGCUCACUGUGUGUUCUUUUGUUCUUCUAAUCAUCUCAUACACUAUCAUCCUAAUGACCAUCCAGCAUCGCCCUUUAGAUAAGUCGUCCAAAGCUCUGUCCACUUUGACUGCUCACAUUACAGUAGUUCUUUUGUUCUUUGGACCAUGUGUCUUUAUUUAUGCCUGGCCAUUCCCCAUCAAGUCAUUAGAUAAAUUCCUUGCUGUAUUUUAUUCUGUGAUCACCCCUCUCUUGAACCCAAUUAUAUACACACUGAGGAACAAAGACAUGAAGACGGCAAUAAGACAGCUGAGAAAAUGGGAUGCACAUUCUAGUGUAAAGUUUUAGAUCUUAUAUAACUGUGAGAUUAAUCUCAGAUAAUGACACAAAAUAUAGUGAAGUUGGUAAGUUAUUUAGUAAAGCUCAUGAAAAUUGUGCCCUCCAUUCCCAUAUAAUUUAUUAAUUGUCUAGGAACUUCCACAUACAUUGCCUCAAUUUAUCUUUCAACAACUUGUGUGUUAUAUUUUGGAAUACAGAUACAAAGUUAUUAUGCUUUCAAAAUAUUCUUUUGCUAAUUCUUAGAACAAAGAAAGGCAUAAAUAUAUUAGUAUUUGUGUACAUCUGUUCCUUCCUGUGUGACCCUAAGUUUAGUAGAAGAAAGGAGAGAAAAUAUAGCCUAGCUUAUAAAUUUAAAAAAAAAUUUAUUUGGUCCAUUUUGUGAAAAACAUAAAAAAAGAACUGUCACAUCUUAAUUUAAAAAAUAUAUGCUUAGUGGUAAGGAGAUAUAUGUCAACUUUUAAGAGGUUGAAAAACAAACGCCUCCCAUUAUAAGUUUAUACUUCACCUCCCACCACUAUAACAACCCAGAAUCCAUGAGGGCAUUAUCAGGAGUGAGUGGAAGAGUAAGUUUGCCAAUGUGAAAUGUGCCUUCUAGGUCCUAGACAUCUGUGGUAUAACUGCUCAUAAGCAGUAGAAAGAAUUUAGAGGGAUCCAGGCUCUCAUCACGUUGGCACAAAGUAUAUUACUUGGAUCCAUCUAUGUCAUUUUCCAUGGUUAAUGUUUAAAACCACAGGCUUUAAAGUAAAAAACAAAGAGCUGGAUUCAACUCUACUGACUCUUAUUAAUCAUGAUUUUGGGCACAUUACGUAGCUUUCAUGAGCUUUAGUUUCUACAUUUAUAAACAGGAGAUUAUACCUAUUAUGCACGGUUAUUAUGAAGGAAAAUGACAAAAUAGAUAUAAAUCAAAUAGCCCACUUCGAGACAUAUUAAGCAUGAAUAAACAUUAGAUACUAUUAAAAUCCUAUAUAUUAACAAAGCCAAAAGUUUCAAACUUUACUUUUUCCCAACAUUCUUGUGAAAUAUGACACAUCCCAAUCUUAACAGAUGCUCAUUUGGGAUACUGUACUUGUGAGUGGAAGUGUGUAUAUUUGUGUGCAAGUGUGUACUCAUAUACUUCCACCUUACCACCCUAGAAAGGCAUGAUGAAAAUUUAAGAUAGAAGGAAAAUAUAAAUUGAAAAAAAAAAACCUUAACAAAUGAUUCUGACAAAUAUCUUCUCUUUCCAGGGAGAAUCACUGAGCCAGAAUAAAAUUGAACACUAAAUAUUCUAAGAAAAAAGGAAUCUAGUUUGUCAAAAUGUGACUUGAAUUAAUAGAUAAGGAGAGUCAGAUGAUAAGAGGGUCAAAAUUAUGUUUAUCUUAGGAAAAGUAGAAUAGAAAAUUUAUAAGCAGAUUAAAAACACAUAAUAAAAGUAGUAAAUAAUAAUGACAGUAUCUCAAAUCAGUGCAGGGGGGAAAGGCCUACUAAUGUGAUGGUGGGAUAAUUGGAUAGCAAUAUGGGAAAAGAUAUAUUUAAUUUAUUUGCUACACCAAAUGCCAGGACAAUCUCUAAGUGAAUUCAAGACAUAAC